AGUCUCCACUGCUGCCGCCGUCGCCGCCACCCGAGCCGGAGCGGGCUGGGCCGCCAAGGCAAGAUGGUGGACUACAGCGUGUGGGACCACAUUGAGGUGUCUGAUGAUGAAGACGAGACGCACCCCAACAUCGACACGGCCAGUCUCUUCCGCUGGCGGCAUCAGGCCCGGGUGGAACGCAUGGAGCAGUUCCAGAAGGAGAAGGAGGAACUGGACAGGGGCUGCCGCGAGUGCAAGCGCAAGGUGGCCGAGUGCCAGAGGAAACUGAAGGAGCUGGAGGUGGCCGAGGGCGGCAAGGCAGAGCUGGAGCGCCUGCAGGCCGAGGCACAGCAGCUGCGCAAGGAGGAGCGGAGCUGGGAGCAGAAGCUGGAGGAGAUGCGCAAGAAGGAGAAGAGCAUGCCCUGGAACGUGGACACGCUCAGCAAAGACGGCUUCAGCAAGAGCAUGGUAAAUACCAAGCCCGAGAAGACGGAGGAGGACUCAGAGGAGGUGAGGGAGCAGAAACACAAGACCUUCGUGGAAAAAUACGAGAAACAGAUCAAGCACUUUGGCAUGCUUCGCCGCUGGGAUGACAGCCAAAAGUACCUGUCAGACAACGUCCACCUGGUGUGCGAGGAGACAGCCAAUUACCUGGUCAUUUGGUGCAUUGACCUAGAGGUGGAGGAGAAAUGUGCACUCAUGGAGCAGGUGGCCCACCAGACAAUCGUCAUGCAAUUUAUCCUGGAGCUGGCCAAGAGCCUAAAGGUGGACCCCCGGGCCUGCUUCCGGCAGUUCUUCACUAAGAUUAAGACAGCCGAUCGCCAGUACAUGGAGGGCUUCAACGACGAGCUGGAAGCCUUCAAGGAGCGUGUGCGGGGCCGUGCCAAGCUGCGCAUCGAGAAGGCCAUGAAGGAGUACGAGGAGGAGGAGCGCAAGAAGCGGCUCGGCCCCGGCGGCCUGGACCCCGUCGAGGUCUACGAGUCCCUCCCUGAGGAACUCCAGAAGUGCUUCGAUGUGAAGGACGUGCAGAUGCUGCAGGACGCCAUCAGCAAGAUGGACCCCACCGACGCAAAGUACCACAUGCAGCGCUGCAUUGACUCUGGCCUCUGGGUCCCCAACUCUAAGGCCAGCGAGGCCAAGGAGGGAGAGGAGGCAGGUCCUGGGGACCCAUUACUGGAAGCUGUUCCCAAGACGGGCGAUGAGAAGGAUGUCAGUGUGUGACCUGCCCCAGCUACCACCGCCACCUGCUUCCAGGCCCCUAUGUGCCCCUUUUCAGAAAACAGAUAGAUGCCAUCUCGCCCGCUCCUGACUUCCUCUACUUGCGCUGCUCGGCCCAGCCUGGGGGGCCCGCCCAGCCCUCCCUGGCCUCUCCACUGUCUCCACUCUCCAGCGCCCAUUCAAGUCUCUGCUUUGAGUCAAGGGGCUUCACUGCCUGCAGCCCCCCAUCAGCAUUAUGCCAAAGGCCCGGGGGUCCGGGGAAGGGCAGAGGUCACCAGGCUGGUCUACCAGGUAGUUGGGGAGGGUCCCCAGCCAAGGGGCCGGCUCUCGUCACUGGGCUCUGUUUUCACUGUUCGUCUGCUGUCUGUGUCUUCUAUUUGGCAAACAGCAAUGAUCUUCCAAUAAAAGAUUUCAGAUGCUC